GUUUGAGGAUGUAGGCACUGGUGUGAAGGAACAUGGCCCUGUAUCAGAGGUGGCGGUGUCUCCGGCUCCAAGGUUUACAGGCUUGCAGGCUACACACGGCAGUUGUGUCGACCCCUCCACGCUGGUUGGCAGAGCGGCUUGGCCUUUUUGAGGAGCUGUGGGCUGCUCAGGUAAAGAGAUUAGCAAGCAUGGCACAGAAGGAACCCCGGACUAUUAAGAUAUCACUUCCUGGAGGCCAGAAAAUUGAUGCUGUGGCAUGGAACACAACCCCCUACCAACUAGCCCGGCAGAUCAGUUCAACACUGGCAGAUACUGCAGUGGCUGCUCAAGUGAAUGGAGAACCUUAUGAUCUGGAGCGGCCCUUGGAGACAGAUUCUGACCUCAGAUUUCUGACAUUCGAUUCCCCAGAGGGGAAAGCAGUGUUCUGGCACUCCAGCACCCAUGUCCUGGGGGCAGCAGCUGAACAAUUCCUAGGUGCUGUUCUCUGCAGAGGUCCAAGUACAGAAUAUGGCUUUUACCAUGAUUUCUUCCUGGGAAAGGAGAGGACAAUCCGGGGCUCAGAGCUGCCUGUUUUGGAGCGGAUUUGCCAGGAACUUACAGCUGCUGCUCGACCCUUCCGGAGGCUAGAGGCUUCACGGGAUCAGCUUCGCCAGUUGUUCAAGGAUAACCCCUUUAAGCUUCACUUGAUUGAGGAGAAAGUGACAGGUCCAACAGCAACAGUAUAUGGGUGUGGCACAUUGGUUGACCUUUGCCAGGGCCCCCACCUUCGGCAUACUGGACAGAUUGGAGGACUGAAGCUGCUAUCGAACUCAUCAUCCUUAUGGAGGUCUUCAGGGGCCCCAGAGACACUGCAGAGAGUGUCAGGGAUUUCCUUCCCCACAACAGAAUUGCUGAGGGUCUGGGAAGCAUGGAGGGAGGAAGCAGAAUUGCGGGACCACCGGCGCAUUGGGAAGGAACAGGAGCUCUUCUUCUUCCAUGAACUGAGCCCUGGGAGCUGCUUCUUCCUGCCACGAGGGACAAGGGUGUAUAAUGCACUAGUGGCGUUUAUCAGGGCUGAGUAUGCCCAUCGUGGUUUCUCCGAGGUGAAAACUCCCACACUGUUUUCUACGAAGCUCUGGGAACAGUCAGGGCACUGGGAGCAUUAUCAGGAAGACAUGUUUGCCGUGCAGCCCCCAGGCUCUGACAGGCCUCCCAGCUCCCAGAGUGACGAUUCUACCAGGCAUAUCACAGAUACACUCGCCCUCAAGCCUAUGAACUGCCCUGCACACUGCCUGAUGUUCGCCCACCGGCCCAGAUCCUGGCGGGAACUGCCCCUGCGACUAGCUGACUUUGGGGCUCUACACCGGGCCGAAGCCUCUGGUGGUCUGGGGGGACUGACCCGACUGCGGUGCUUCCAGCAGGAUGACGCUCACAUCUUCUGUACAACAGAUCAGCUGGAAGCAGAGAUCCAAAGCUGUCUUGAUUUCCUCCGUUCCGUCUAUGCCGUUCUUGGCUUCUCCUUCCGCCUGGCACUGUCCACCCGGCCAUCUGGCUUCCUGGGGGACCCUUGCCUUUGGGACCAGGCCGAACAGGUCCUUAAACAGGCCCUGAAGGAAUUUGGAGAACCCUGGGACCUCAACUCUGGAGAUGGUGCCUUCUAUGGACCUAAGAUUGACGUGCACCUCCACGAUGCCCUGGGCCGGCCACAUCAGUGUGGGACAAUUCAGCUUGACUUCCAACUGCCCCUGAGAUUUGACCUCCAGUAUAAGGGGCAGGCGGGUGCCCUGGAGCGUCCAGUCCUCAUUCACCGAGCAGUGCUCGGUUCUGUGGAAAGACUGUUGGGAGUGCUGGCAGAAAGCUGCGGGGGGAAAUGGCCACUGUGGCUGUCCCCGUUCCAGGUGGUGGUCAUCCCUGUGGGGAGUGAGCAAGAGGAAUACGCCAAAGAGGCACAGCAGAGCCUGCGGGCUGCAGGACUGGUCAGUGACCUGGAUGCAGACUCUGGACUGACCCUCAGCCGGAGAAUCCGCCGGGCCCAGCUUGCCCACUACAAUUUUCAGUUUGUGGUUGGCCAGAAAGAGCAAAGUAAGAGAACAGUGAACAUUCGGACUCGAGAUAAUCGUCGCCUUGGGGAGUGGGACUUGCCUGAGGCUGUGCAGCGACUGGUGGAGCUACAGAACACGAGGGUCCCAAAUGCCGAAGAAAUUUUCUGAGCCUUUGUACAUAGAUGAGGCAAAAACCUGCGAGUGCCAUCAGCCUCCCUCACAUGGGAGACCCCAACCCAGCUGACAAUGUGGAGCCCCCAGAACUUCAGAACUGUGUGGAGGCACAUGUCUGCUCUCCUGAAAAGAGACUUGGUUUGGGGACCCCACAAAAGGAGGGAAGCUGUAGCUGUUUGGAUGUGAGGAGAAUGAAACUACAAAAAAAAAUAAAUUGGGCCAGGCGCAGUGGCUCAUGCCUGUAAUCCCAGCACUCUGGGAGGCUGAGGCGGACGGAUCAUGAGGUCAGGAGAUCAAGACCACCCUGGCUAACACGGUGAAACCCUGUCUCUACUAAAAAUACAAAAAAUUAGCCGGGCAUGGUGGCACACGCCUGUAAUCCCAGCUACUCAGGAGGCUGAGGCAGGAGAAUCGCUUGAACCCGGGAGGUAGAGGUUGCAGUGAGCUGAGAUUGCGCCACUGCACCCCCCUAGGCGACAGAGCGAGACUCUGUCUCUAAAUAAAUAAAUAAAUAAAUAAAUACAAACUGGAA